ACGUGAUCCGACAAACGGCCUCUGCAUAGUGCAGAACAUUCUGCUGCUCUUAAAGGUACAGGCCUCAGGGUCCCUGCUGUAGACGGGGCGGGGGAGAGUACGAUGGGUGGGGCGUGGUGGGUCGUAGGGCGCUCGAGAUGGAGCCCCCAGCUUCCUUGAUGGAUCGCGGGGCGCGAGUGCCCUAGACAAGCCGGAGCUGGGACCGGCAAUCGGGCGUUGAUCCUUGUCACCUGUCGCAGACCCUCAUCCCUCCCGUGGGAGCCCCCUUUGGACACUCUAUGACCCUGGACCCUCGGGGGACCUGAACUUGAUGCGAUGGGAGGCUGUGCAGGCUCGCGGCGGCGCUUUUCGGAUUCCGAGGGCUGCUGGGCCUUUGCAACAACUUCUCUUAUGUGGUGAUGCUGAGUGCCGCCCACGACAUCCUUAGCCACAAGAGGACAUCGGGAAACCAGAGCCAUGUGGACCCAGGCCCAACGCCGAUCCCCCACAACAGCUCAUCACGAUUUGACUGCAACUCUGUCUCUACGGCUGCUGUGCUCCUGGCGGACAUCCUCCCCACACUCGUCAUCAAAUUGUUGGCUCCUCUUGGCCUUCACCUGCUGCCCUACAGCCCCCGGGUUCUCGUCAGUGGGAUUUGUGCUGCUGGAAGCUUCGUCCUGGUUGCCUUUUCUCAUUCUGUGGGGACCAGCCUGUGUGGUGUGGUCUUCGCUAGCAUCUCAUCAGGCCUUGGGGAGGUCACCUUCCUCUCCCUCACUGCCUUCUACCCCAGGGCCGUGAUCUCCUGGUGGUCCUCAGGGACUGGGGGAGCUGGGCUGCUGGGGGCCCUGUCCUACCUGGGCCUCACCCAGGCCGGCCUCUCCCCUCAGCAGACCCUGCUGUCCAUGCUGGGUAUCCCUGCCCUGCUGCUGGCCAGCUAUUUCUUGUUGCUCACAUCUCCUGAGGCCCAGGACCCUGGAGGGGAAGAAGAAGCAGAGAGCGCAGCCCGGCAGCCCCUCAUAAGAACCGAGGCCCCGGAGUCGAAGCCAGGCUCCAGCUCCAGCCUCUCCCUUCGGGAAAGGUGGACAGUGUUCAAGGGUCUGCUGUGGUACAUUGUUCCCUUGGUCGUAGUUUACUUUGCCGAGUAUUUCAUUAACCAGGGACUUUUUGAACUCCUCUUUUUCUGGAACACUUCCCUGAGUCACGCUCAGCAAUACCGCUGGUACCAGAUGCUGUACCAGGCUGGCGUCUUUGCCUCCCGCUCUUCUCUCCGCUGCUGUCGCAUCCGUUUCACCUGGGCCCUGGCCCUGCUGCAGUGCCUCAACCUGGUGUUCCUGCUGGCAGACGUGUGGUUCGGCUUUCUGCCAAGCAUCUACCUCGUCUUCCUGAUCAUUCUGUAUGAGGGGCUCCUGGGAGGCGCAGCCUACGUGAACACCUUCCACAACAUCGCCCUGGAGACCAGUGAUGAGCACCGGGAGUUUGCAAUGGCGGCCACCUGCAUCUCUGACACACUGGGGAUCUCCCUGUCGGGGCUCCUGGCUUUGCCUCUGCAUGACUUCCUCUGCCAGCUCUCCUGAUACUCGGGAUCCUCAGGACGCAGGUCACAUUCACCUGUGGGCAGAGGGACAGGUCAGACACCCAGGCCCACCCCAGAGACCCUCCAUGAACUGUGCUCCCAGCCUUCCCGGCAGGUCUGGGAGUAGGGAAGGGCUGAAGCCUUGUUUCCCUUGCAGGGGGGCCAGCCAUUGUCUCCCACUUGGGGAGUUUCUUCCUGGCAUCAUGCCUUCUGAAUAAAUGCCGAUUUUAUCCAUGGACUUCUUAUAUCGUUUUUGUCUCUAAAAAGAAACUUUUAUUAUGAAAGUAAUACAUGCCCACUUUCCUAUAUAUAGACAGCAUAAAGAAGGUAUGUCAGCAGAUUUCUCCCUUUUUUGUUUGUUUGUUUGUUUGUUUGUUUGUUUUGACAGAGUCUCACUCUGUCACCUAGGCUGGAGUGCAAUGGCGUGAUCUUGGCUCACUGCAACCUCCACUUCCCGGUUCAAGCAAUUCUCCUGCCUCAGCCUCCCGAGUAGCUGGGAUUACAGGUGGUCACUACCAUGUCUGGCUAAUUUUUAUAUUUUUAGUACAGACGACAUUUUGCCAUGUUGGCCAGGCUGGUCUCAAACUCAUGACCUCAGGUGAUCCGCCCACCUUGGCCUCCCAAAGUGCUGAGAUUACAGGUGUGAGCCACUGUACCUGGCCUCUGCCAUCUUUGAGGCCUUACGUAUUCAUUCAUUCAUGCAUUCAUUGUUUGGGACAAUCUGUAAACAAUCAUGUUGGACAUUCUUUCCAGCAUGAAAGUUUUCAGAGAAGUGGAAAGAAUUGUGCAGUGAAUCAUCCUGAGUAUGCGCCACCCUGUUCUAUGUUAACAUUUUGUUACAGUUGUUUUAUCAUGUAGUCCAGCCCCCAUCAAAUCUAUGUAUUCACUGUUCCAUCAGUGAGUAGAUAGAGCUAAUGAAUGGCAGGGUUGGCACCUGAGGCAUUUUAUUUUAUUAUUUUUUUUUAUUUUUAGAGACAGGGUUGCACUCUGUCACCCAGGCUGAAGUACAGUGGCACAGUCAUGGCUCACUGUAGCCUUGACCUCCUAGACUCAAACAAUCCUCACACCUUGGCCUCCCAAGCAGCUGGGACUGCAAGUGCAUGCCACCAAGCCCAGCUAAUUUUUUUUUUUUUUUUUGUAGAGACGCGAUCUUCCUAUGUUACCCAGGCUGGUCUUGAACUCUUGAGCUCAAGCAGUCCUGCCUUGGCCUCCCAAAGUACUGAGAUUACAAGCAUGAGCCACUGCUCCUGGCAUCCUGUUAUUUAGGUACAGUUUUUAUACACAGUAAAAUGUAUAAAUUGUUACAUAUUUUUACAGUAAACUGAGUCUGGGCCAGGCACUGUGGCUCACACCUGUAAUCCCAGCACUUUGGGAGGCUGAGGCGGGCAGAUCACCUGAGGUCAGGAGUUUGAGACCAGCCUGCACAACGUGACAAAACCCCGUCUCUACGAAAAAUAUAAAAAAUUAGCCAGGUGUGGUGGCUUGCACCUGUAGUCCCAGCUACUUGGAAGGCUGAGGCGCAAGAAUUGCUUGAACCCAGGAGGCGGAGGUUGUGGUGAGCUGAAAUUGCACCACUGCACUCCAGCCUGGGCAACAGAGCAAGACUCUGUCUCAAAAAAAAAAACAAAAAAACUGAGUCUGACUUAGUGUUUCUCAUACUUCAUUGUUACCCUUUCUACUAUAUUUGCCAUAUCUGAACCUAACAGUACUUUUAUUUACUUAAUAUUUUUCAUUAAAGCAACUAACCUUUAAUAUACAUUCAGUUAUUUUAAAGGGAAACAUUAUUAAAAUCAUGAGUUUGAGGUGAUAUAUAUGUAUUUUCUACUUUACUUUAAAUAGUUAUGUAACUAUUGGAGUUUAAAAUGAACAUGCAAGUUCCCCCUGAGACUACUCCAUUACGACCAGUGAUGUUUGUGGACCCAGAUCUAGGAAAUGCUGACCCACUGGUUAAUAGCAUGGGCUUUGGGGGCAGAAGGAACUGACUUUCAGGUGCCAACCCUGCCAUUCACUAGCUCUAUUACCUUGGGCAAGUCACUUCACCUCUCUGCACCUCAGUUUCCUGAUCUGUCCAAUGGGAUAAUAGUAGCACCAGCAUUUCAUAAGUUGCUUUUGGAAACUACAUGAGAUCAUGUCAACACUCAAUAAACAUCAGCUCUGAUCAUGCUA